GAGGACCCGGCAACUGUCUCUGCUCUUUGAAUGUAUGUUUCGAGCCUGCCCCUUGCCAGGUGAGAGUUCUGUUUGGCUGUAAGUGCCUGUGCUGCUCUUGAUGAAUGACUGUUGACGUCAGCUGGCCCUCCUGUGCUCGCCUGUAUGCCUGAGGAGGCACACCUGACCUCUGCUCUAAGCCUUGUCUCAUGCCAGCAUUGAUUUCCUAGCUUGUUAACAUUCUCAAGAUGAAGACUGUUUUCUUUACUAGUAUGUGACUCACUUGGUCUAUGUGGGGAGAAGACCCUGGAGUUGGAAGCUUUCCUGGUUUGUAGGUGGAGUGCCUUUGGAAAUGCUGGGGUGUGCUGGGGAAGUCUGUGGCCCAGGGUGAGGACCACCGCCCGCUCCAGCUGCUCUGCCACCAGCCACCUCGCUCCAGGCGUGCUCCUCACUCUCCUGGGCUGGCUGCUUCUAUGGCCAGUUCCGGGAGUGGAUGAACGUUUGAUUCCUUACCGGGGACCUUUUGUGGGAGGUGCUGGGAGGGCACCGGGACCUCAGAGUGAGCGCUGCGUCAGGGCUCCCUGGGCUUUCAAACCUCCUCAGCUUCUGGGAUGGGAUGUGUGCGUUUGGCGCUGUCCUGAAGAGAUGCAAGGCCCUUCCUGCCAGCCCUCGUGAAUGCUGGGAGGUCAGCCGGCCCUCGUGAAUGCUGCUGCUGCUGGCAAGGCUUCACUUGGGGAUGAUCACCUGGCCACAGGUGUCUGUCUUUUUCUGGACUUUAAAAAUACUUUUUAUUGGCCAGGCACGGUGGCUCACGCCUGUAAUCCCAGCACUUUGGGAGGCCAAGGCGGGUGGAUCACGAGAUCAGGAGAUCGAGACCAUCCUGGCUAACACGGUGAAACCCCGUCUAUACUAAAAAUAAAAAAAUUAGCCGGGCAUGGUGGCGGGCGCCUGUAGUCCCAGCUUCUUGGGAGGCUGAGGCAGGAGAAUGGCGUGAACCCGGGAGGCGGAGGUUGCUGUGAGCCAACAUCAUGCCACUGCACCCCAGCCUGGGCGACAGAGCAAGACUCCAUCUCAAAAAAAAAAAAAUUUUUUUUAAUUUAAGUAUUUUCAGACCUCCAGCAAAGUUGCAAAAUUCUACGAAUAAGUCCUGUGUACCCUUUAUUCAUUUCACCACAUGGCACAAUCUCGCCCCCGGCCCCCCCAUGUAUUACUUUUUUUUCUGAGACAUGAAUGUAAGUUGUAAACAUUGUGCCCUUUUAUCCCUGAAAACUAAUGUUAUUUCCUAAAAUUACUGUCCCUCAACAUAAAGACAUUCUCUUAGAUGACUACAGCACAGACAUCCCGGUGAGGAAGUAUACCGCGACGCCGCUCUCUAAUCUCAGUGUCCUGUUCCGCAUUUCCCAUUCCCGACUGUCUUUUAGGGCAAAGGACAAAUAAAAUCUGGUUCUAGAGCUUCGAGCACCUAGUUGUUGUGUCUUGCUAGUUUCCUUUAAUCUGAACCAUUCUCAGCCUUCUUUGUCUUUCUGAACCGUGGUGUUUUGAGUACAGGCCAGGUCUUUCAUAGAAUGUGUCUGAUGUGGGUUUGCCCAGUGUUUCCCAGGAUUGUGUGCAGGUCGUGGAGCGACGCAGGUGACUGACAAGUGUCCUUAGGAAUUGAAUUGUGGUGGUUUUUUGUCCAUCUUCAAGUUACUGCUCACCAGACUGCAAGCAUGUCUUGCAGGGAGAGACCCUAAGGUGCUGCAUGUACCUCCCAUCACAUCCCACCAGGGUCUUCAGCAUCUGCCAUGGCCCACGCUUAGCUAGUACUGCACGGUGGGUGCCAAAUGGUGGUUUUCUAACUCCAUCAUUUCCUCUCUUGAUUAUUUCAGUUUCUGCUGUAAGGAGGUGCUUCACUUUCCUGUCCGUCCACACAGUUAUCUGUCCAUUUACUUUACAAAAAAAAAAACUUAAAAAAAAAAUAGAGAUGGGGGUCUCGCUAUGUUGCCCAGGCUGGUCUUGAACUCGUGGGCUCAAGCAGUCCUCCUGACUUGGCCUCCCAAAGUGCUAGGAUUACAGGCGUGGGCCACCGCCCCCAGCCUGUCUGUCUGUUUUUAAGUACUAAUUUACGGACUCUUAUUUGAGUCUCUGGACUGUAAUCCAUUCCUAUCAUUAUUUAUUUUGUUGCUCACAUUGUCCCAAGUUUGUCCAGUGGGGUCCCCCUAGGCUGGUUCUGAGUCCUGGGGCGUGGGCACCUCUUCAGGAAGACCUUCCCCAUUCACUGGAUGGUCUGCUUACCUUGCCUUGUCCCUUCCCAGGGCCGGAAUCGGCUUUCUCCAGGGAGCCCUGGUUCUUUUCAUUGGAAGUUAGAAAACAAAAUCAGUCAUUAUCUGUUCCCCUCACCAUCAACUUACCAACUUUUUUUGCUAUUUGACGUAAUUUUAUUUGUUUGAAACAGUUAAACUUGGUGUUUUGCAAAACUAUGGAGUUAUGCUCACGUAUGUGAGGACUUAAAAGUAAUGUCUGAAGAGUUGUUAAAGUGUUGAGAUUUUCUUUUCCUAUUUUAGCUUUAUUAUAUCGCCAUCUUUUAAAAAGAGCUUUCUAAAAACAAACUACCCAGCGUGUUUAGCAGGCUCCAGUUUACCCUUCCACAGCCCCCUUCCUCCACCACCCCUUCCUUAUCCGUAACCUGGAAGUGGGUGGUCCAUCAGCGUGUUAGCCUAGGACAGUGUGUAAAAUGGCCUUGAGCACUGGAGGAGAUGUGCUCGGCAGUUAGCUGCCUGCUGUGGUCCAGUGGUUAAGAUACUCCCUCAGCCUCAGCUGCUCCCGUGUGUUGUCACCCCAGGGCUUCCGGAGUGGGCACAGAAGUUACAGUUUCUGUGCUAGAACGUGUUAACUAGAGAGGAGCAUGGCAUGCCCAGCUGCCUUGUCUUGUGAUGGUCAUCAGUGCACCUUUCAACAUGGCUGGAAAGACAGGAGUGCAGAUGGAGGAGUCCCCUGUUAACUGUCCCCGGGGGUGCAGAGUCCACUUAUCGGGAUGGCAGAGAGAGACAAAGGCCUUUUACAACAGUGUCCAUACAGAGCAGGAAUCGGGGUACGUCCUAUCCUGUUGUCACAGGAUCCCUUGAGUGUCCCUUUGCUGGUCAUAAACCUCUGCAGCCAGCGGCGCCUCUGCUUGAGUUUCACUUGCACCUGCUGGGCUCAUUCUGCCCACUCGGCCCAGCAGGCUGUACUUGGCUCAUGCUACCGGCCCAGAUCCCACACCUUCCGAGGGCAAGCCAGGAGUGGAGCAGCGAGGCGUGUGUUGACGAGCAAGCAUGGUGUGGGGCCACUGUGCACAGCCAGGCCUGCUUGGCUGCUGUGGUGGGGCAGGCAGCUCCAGGCUCUGGCUCUGUGCAGAGCUGUGGCUGGAUGAGGCAUACCACAAGCAGUUUACACUGCAGGCGCUGGCGUCUAGAUGAGGGGAACACGGUGGUGCCCCAAAACUCGGAGUCACCAGCAACUGCAGAGCCCCAAGGGGAUAGGGUGGGAGAGUGUGCUAUAGCUCUCUUGCUGUCACCACCCACAGUACGGGCUGGGGUGUGUUCCCAGCUCGUUCAGUUCUGCCGCUUUCGCCCUGGCCUGCAGCUCCCAGGCUGGCCUGGCUCCACUGCUGCUUGCCAUCACACGGGGCAGCCGCCGACACCAGCGGAGGGCAGGAGGGCUACAGUGUUACAGCUCUGGCUUGAGGAAUCCCAAGGUUUGGGUCCCCAGAAGGAUCACCGCUCUUCACUCCCGCAGUUCAGCGAACGGGAGCGUGUCACUGCCUGCAGCUCAGUGAACCGGCCAGGAACAUGUUACAGCCCUUUUUGCACCCGCUGUUGCGUGGGUCCCGAGUUCUUGUCUUGGGUCCAGGAAGAAUGAGGUUACAUGGACAACUGGAGGGGAGCAAGGUGGAGAAGAGUUUUAUUGAGCAGCAGAACAGCUCUCAGCGGAGAGGAGACCCAAAGUCAGUAGCUCCUACUGGCAGGGAGGCAGUCCUGUUGUGUGGCUGAGUCUGGGGGUUUAUGUGGGCUCAGAAUGGAGGAAGUGCAUGAAGUGCAUGCUGAUUGGUCCAUGGGUAGGUCUGGAAAAAACACCAUUUGAUUGGCUAAAAGGCAUCAAGGAAGUUCUCACUCCAGGUUGUGGAUUCUGCCGGGAACUGGCAGCCCGGUUUUCAGGCUUCAGGCGGCCUUUGGCUUGAAGGUCAGGUUUCACCGGGGACCUGCUCCUAUCUGCCUAGGAAUUUGUCUGCCAUUAUCACUUUUAUUUCUUCAACUGUCACUCCAUUGCCUGCCAUUCAUUGUUGCCUCCCUGUGGGAGGGGUGUUGGAGCCAGGUUAUCAAAGAAAGGCUGAGAUUUCUUGUCACGUCUUUCUGUUAAUUUUUAAUUACUGUGGCGAUGAUCACAGAUGGUUCUGCUCUUUCCCUCCUGCUACCCCCUUAAGUUUACCACAGGCAGGAAAGAAGAGCAGAGUCACAUGUUGGUUUCAACGUGCAUUGUACUCCUGAAGUCAUAGCAGAGCCCGUGUGUGGUAGCUUGUUCCCAUGGGCAGCUGUAAUUCUUAGUUUUAGAUGGAGGGUGGCUGUGAUUCUCUUCGACCUGUUCUGCACCCUCCACCCUGUAGUAUCAGAAAUGAAAGAUCUGUGCUGUGCAAGAAGGUUGAGAACAUGCGUUUAUGUGACAGCCCCAGGCUGGGGAUGGCCGUGCUGAAUCAGGAUCUCAGGCACCCAGCAUUGUUUUAGGUGAGCAUUCCUUCUUUUUACAGAGUGGACUGGCAUCUUUGUUAGCAGCUUGUUCUGUAUCUUUCCCACGUGUAGCGGUUCACAAUUUAAAAACAAUCCUCGCAGUACCAAAAACUGAUUUCAGAGGGUUCUAGAAAGAUAGUGGGGCAGGAAGACCAGGAAUUCAUCUCCUCACCUAGACAACAGUUCCACUGGCAGAAUCUGUCUGAUGUAACUAUUUUGGAACUCUGGAGUCUACUGAAGGUUUGCAACUUCUAGGCGGGAAGCUGGGACGGUUAAUUUCAGUCAGUUUCAGCUCUGCUGCCCACUGCCUUCCUCAGCCCUGUGGUGCAGGGUGUGCGGUGUUCCUGGAACAGUGUGCGUGCAGCUUGUGGGAGCCAGGGUGAGCAAAGAGGACCUUGUCCCCAGGUGCAUACAGAGAGGCCCUCUCAUCCGGUUGUAAGCCUUUCUUCCAUGUGACGGCCAAGAAAUCUAAAGGGCCAGUGCUCUUUUUAUCUCCCCACUUCAUUUUUAUUGUUUUCUCCUUUUGGGAGCCAGACAUUAAAGACUAGGAUAUUCAGAAGCAACUGUGUAUAUGGGGUAAAUUAUAAAGUGACUGCAUGUGCCCAGGGAAAGGCACAGGCUAAGGGAAGACAUGAAAAGACCUUAAGUUUAAAUCUCAGGCUCACCCUCCUCACAGAGACAGCCUACAACUAUAAAAAAUGACAACAACAAAAACACCCCAAAACCAGUAACAGCAACAAAACAGUACACCCUGGAAAAGGAGGAGAAUCAGCUUUUCAGAGUUUCUACAUUAUUGGAUUCAAAUGUCCAGUUUUCAGCAUAGAACUACAAGGCAUACAAAGAAACAGGAAGGUAUGGCCCAAUCAGAUGCAAAAAUAAGUCAACAGAAACUGUUCCCAGAAAAGAUCUGAUGCCAGAUCCACCAGACAAAGACUUUAAAGUAACUGUCUUAGAUAUGGUCAGAUCCUAAAGGAAGGUAUGGAGAGAGUCAAGAAAAUGAUGUAUGAUCAAAAUGGAAAUACCAAUAAAGAGCUAGAAAACGUAAAAAGGAACCAAAAGAAAUUCUGGAGCUAAAAAGUAUAAUAAGUGAAAUGAAAAAUUCACUAGAGGAAAUCAAAGGCAGAUCUGAACAGACGGAAGAAAGAGAUAGCAAACUUGAAGAUAGGACAGUGAAAAUAAUCAAGUUUGAGAAGCAAACAACAAGACUGAAGGGAAGUGAGCAGAGCCUGGGGACCUGUGGGCAUCAUCAGGAGGACCAAACAGGGAUUGUGGGAGUCCAGGAAGAAGAGAGUAAGAAAAGGGUGGAGAGAAUAUCUGAUGAAACCCAUGAGUAUAAACACCCAGGGAACCUGGUGAACUCCAGUAAGAUGAACUCAAAGAGACCCACAGUAGACACGUUAUACUUGAGACACUUCUGUAGAAAGACAAAGAGAAUCUUGAAAGCAGAUGAGAAAAGAGACUCAUCACAUACACGUUUCCUCAGUGAGAUCAUUGGCAGGUUUCUCAUCAGAAACUUUGGGGGACAGAAUAUAUCACCGGUAUAUUAAGAGUGAUAAAAAAAUCUUUCAACCAAGUAUCCAUAUCCAUGGAAACUGUCCUUUAAGAGUGCAGAAGAAAUUAAGAUAUUCUCAGAUAAACAAAAGCUGAGGGAAUUUGUUACCACCUGACCUGGACCUGCAAGAAAUACUUAAAGGAGCCUAGCAGGUUGAAAAGAAAGAACACUAGACAGUAACUUGAAGCCAUAUGGAGAAGUAAAGACAUGGGCAGUUAUAAAAGCUAGUAUUGUAACAGUGGUUUGUACCUCCACUUUUUGUUUUCUGUAAGAUCUAAGAGACAAAUCCGUUUAAAAAAUUAGUCUGCAAGCUAGUAUCAUUGCAACUUUGGUUUGUAACUCCACAUUUUUCCUACAUAACAAGAGACUAAUGCAUUUAAACGAAUUGUUUAUGUUUUGGGGCACAGCAUGAAUAAAGAUGUAGUUUUGUGACAUCAGCAAAUGAAAGGGGUGGGAACAGAUAUGUAAAGGAGCAGAGUUUUUCUGUGUUACUGAAGUUAAGCUGGCAUAAAUUUAAAUUAGAAUGUUAUUACUUUAGGAUGUUAAAUGUAAUCCCCAUGGUAACCACAAAGAAAAUAGCUAUAGAACAUACACAAAAGGAAAUGAGAAAAGAAUUUAAACAUUCCACUAUAAAAAAUCAACUAAAUAUAAAAGAAGACAGUAGUGCAAGAAAUGAGGGACGAAAAAAGCUAUAAUACGUGUAGCAAACAUAGCAAAAUGACAGAAGUAAAUCCUCAUCAAUAGUUGUUUUAAAUGUAAACAGAUGAAGAUUUCCAAUCAAAAGACGAAGAUUGGCAGUGCUAUGGUUUGGAUGUGGUUUGUCCACACCAAAGCUCAUGUUGAAAUGAGAUCCCCAAUAUGGCAGUGUUGUGAGGUGGGGCCUAGCUUGAGGUGAUUGGUCAUGUGUGUGGAUUCCUCAUGAAUAGAUCAGUGCCCUCCCUCCAGGUGAGUGAAUUCUCGCUCUUAGUUGCCUUGAGAGUGAGGUGUUUGAAAGAAUCUGGCUUCCUUGGUUUCUCUGUCUCUUCCUUCUUCUCUCACCAUGUGAUCGCUUGCACAUGCCUGCUCCCUUUCCAAUUUCCACCAUGAGCCAGAGCAUGAAGCCCUACCAGGUGUACCUGCUCAAUAUUAAACUUUCCAGCCACCAGACUCAGGAGACAAAUCUCUUUAUCUUUUAUGGCAACACUAAAUGGACAAAGGCAGAUGCAUCAAGAGAAAAAAAACAGAUGAUCCUACUACAUGCUGUCUAUAAGAGACCCACCUUAGAUCCAAAGACAGAAAUAGAUUGAAAGUGAAAGGAUGAAAAAAGAUAUUCCAUGCAAACAGUAACCAAAGAGAGCAAGGUGGCUAUCAGACAAAAUUUAAAAAUAAAAAUUUAUUUCUUUUUAAAUAAAAAAAGGUUACAAGAGACUAAGAAGGACAAUAUAUAGUAAUAAAAGUUUCAAUACAAUAAGAAGGUAUAACAAUUACCUGGGUAAACAUUUACAUACCCAACGAAUGAUAGACUAUCAAGAUACAAGAAGUAAAACUGAUAGAAUUGAAGGGAGACAUAGACAAUUCUACAUUAAUAGUUGGAGACCUCAGUAUCCACUUAUCAAUAAUGGAUAGAAUAACCAUAUAGCAAAUAAGAAAGGAAAUGGAGGACUAAACACCAUAAGCCAACUAGAUUUAGCAGACAUACAGAGCACUCUGCCCAACAGCAGCAUGUACACUCUUCUCAAGUGCACCUGGAAGACUUUCUAGGAUCGACCAUAUGUUAGGCCACAAAUAAGUCUCAAUGUUGAUUUUAAAAUACAGAGAUUUGAGCCGGGCGCGAUGGCGCACGCCUGUAAUCCCAGUACUUUGGGAGGCUGACGUGGGUGGAUCACUUGAGGUCAGGAGUUCGAGACCAGCCUGGCCAACAUGGUGAAACCCCAUCUCUACUAAAAAUACAAAAAUUAGCUGGGCGUGGUGGCACGUCCCUGUAAUCCCAGAUACUUGGGAGGCCGAGGCACGAGAAUUACUUGAACCUGGGAGGUGGAGGUUGCAGUGAGCCAAGAUCAUACCACUGCACUCCAGCCUGGGUGACAGAGUGAGCCUGUGUCUCAAAAAAAAAGAAAAAUAUAUACAGAGAUUUGGCUGGGUGUGGUGGCUCAAGCCUGUCAUCCAUGCACUUUGAGAGGCCACGGUGAGCUGGUCACUUGAGCUCAGGAGUUCCAGAGCGGCCUGGGCAACAUAGCAAAACCCUGUCUCUUAAAAAAAAUACAAAAAUUAGCCAGGCAUGGUGGCAAGUGCCUGUGGUUCCAGCUACUCCAGAGCCCCAGAGGCUGAGGUGGGAGGAUUGCUGGAGCCCAGAAGGUCGAGGCUGCAGUGAGCCAUGAUUGUAUCACUGCACUUUAGCCUAGGUGACAGAGUGAGACACUGUCUUAAAAAAUAAUAUAUGUAUAUGUGGAAAAAGACAGAGAUUCAAAACUUACUACAAAGCUAUAGUACUCAAAACAGUGUUAUUCCAGCAUAAAGACAGACAUAUAGGCCAGUGGGCUAGAACAGAGAGCACAGAAAUAAACCUUUGUGUUAUAUGAUCAGUUGAUUUUUGACAAGAGUGCCAAGACCAUUCAACGGGGGAAAGGACAGCUUUCCAACAAAUGGUGCGGGGAAGACUGGAUAUCCACAUGCAGAAGAGUGAUACUGGACCCUUACCUCACACCAUAUGCAGAAGUUAGCCUAAGACAGGUCCAGGACCUAAAUGUAAGACCUAAACAUAUAAAAUUCUGAGAAGAAAACAUAGGACAAAGGCUCCACAACCUUGGAUUUGGCAGUGAUUUCUUGGACAUGACACCAAAAGUGUAGGUAACAAAAAAAAAGGAGACACACUGGGUUUGAUGAGACUUGGUGUCUUUUGAUGCACAAAGCUUUCUAUCUCCUUGUUUCCCUGUUUCCCUGCUUCUUACUGCUGCACUUGGCUAGUCGUAAAGAAAAGACACUGUUAACGGAAUAAAAAGGCACCUGUGGAGUAGGAGAAAAUAUCUGCAAAUCCUAUGUCUGAUGAGGAAUUACUACCCAAAAUAUACAAAAAAAAUCCCACAACUCAACAAUAAAAACAACUUGAUUAAAAAAUCAGCAAAGGAGGCCGGGUGCAGUGGCUUGCGCCUGUAAUCUCAGCACUUUGGGAGGCCGAGGCAGGCAGAUCACCUGAGGUCAGGAGUUCCAGACGAGCCGAGCCAACAUAGUGAAACCCCAUCUCUACUACAAAUACAAAAGUUAGCUGGGCAUAGUGGUGCAUGCCUGUGGUCCCAGGUACUUGGGAGGCUGAGGCAGGAGAAUCACUUGAACCCGAGUGGUAGAGGUUGCAGUGAGCCGAGAUCGGACCACUGCACUCCAGCCUGGGUGACAGAGUGAGACUCUGUCUCAAAAAAAACAACAACAAAAAAAAAACAACAAAAAAAACCCAAAAAAGGCAAAGGACUGGAAUAGACGUUUAUUCAAAGAAGAUGCACAAAUGGCCAGUAAGCCCAUGAAAAGAUGCUCAACGUCACUAAUCAUAAGGUAAAUGCAAAUCAAAACCACAGUGAGAUACCACCGUACACCUGUUGAGGACAGCAACUAUCAAAACAGAAAAUGGCACAUAUCAGUGAGGAUGCGGAGAAAUGGGAACCCUUGUGCACUGCUGGUAGGAAGUGAAACGGUGCAUCUGCUGUGAAAAACUCAAAAAACUAAGUGUGGAACUACCAUGUGAUCCAGCAGUUCCACUGCUGGGCACGUGCCCCAGCAGCACUGAAAGCAGGGUCUUGAAGAGAUGCUUGUACACCCACGUUGAUAGCAGCAUCAACCACAGCAGCCAAAAGGGGGAAGCCACCCGAGGGUCGGCUGUCGGGCGAACGGAUCAGCAAAGUGUCGUGUGCAAAACGCAGUGACGUGUGACUCAGCCUGAGAAGCAGCGAAGCUGGGGCCCGCGCUGCAGCGUGGAUGAGCCUCGGGGACACUGUGCCGAAUGAACAGCUGCAGUAUCUCGGAAGAAAAAACGAAGAAUGGGAACCUAUAGCCUGGUUCCUAAGAAAAAGACCAAAGUAUUAAAACAGAGGACGGUGAUUGAGAUGUUUAAGAGCAUAACUCAUUCCACUGUGGGUUCCAAGGGGGAGAAGGACCUGGGCGCCAGCAGCCUGCACGUGAAUGGGGAGAGCCUGGAGAUGGACUCGGAUGAGGACGACUCAGAGGAGCUCGAGGAGGACGACGGCCAUGGUGCAGAGCAGGCGGCCGCGUUCCCCACAGAGGACAGCAGGACUUCCAAGGAGAGCAUGUCGGAGGCUGAUCGCGCCCAGAAGAUGGACGGGGAGUCCGAGGAGGAGCAGGAGUCCGUGGACACCGGGGAGGAGGAGGAAGGCGGUGACGAGUCUGACCUGAGUUCGGAAUCCAGCAUUAAGAAGAAAUUUCUCAAGAGGAAAGGAAAGACCGACAGUCCCUGGAUCAAGCCAGCCAGGAAAAGGAGGCGGAGAAGUAGAAAGAAGCCCAGCGGUGCCCUCGGUUCUGAGUCGUAUAAGUCAUCUGCAGGAAGCGCUGAGCAGACGGCACCAGGAGACAGCACAGGGUACAUGGAAGUUUCUCUGGACUCCCUGGAUCUCCGAGUCAAAGGAAUUCUGUCUUCACAAGCAGAAGGGUUGGCCAACGGUCCAGAUGUGCUGGAGACAGACGGCCUCCAGGAAGUGCCUCUCUGCAGCUGCCGGAUGGAAACACCGAAGAGUCGAGAGAUCACCACACUGGCCAACAACCAGUGCAUGGCUACAGAGAGCGUGGACCAUGAAUUGGGCCGGUGCACAAACAGCGUGGUCAAGUAUGAGCUGAUGCGCCCCUCCAACAAGGCCCCGCUCCUCGUGCUGUGUGAAGACCACCGGGGCCGCAUGGUGAAGCACCAGUGCUGUCCUGGCUGUGGCUACUUCUGCACAGCGGGUAAUUUUAUGGAGUGUCAGCCCGAGAGCAGCAUCUCUCACCGUUUCCACAAAGACUGUGCCUCUCGAGUCAAUAACGCCAGCUAUUGUCCCCACUGUGGGGAGGAGAGCUCCAAGGCCAAAGAGGUGACGAUAGCUAAAGCAGACACCACCUCGACCGUGACACCAGUCCCCGGGCAGGAGAAGGGCUCGGCCCUGGAGGGCAGGGCCGACACCACAACGGGCAGUGCUGCCGGGCCACCACUCUCGGAGGACGACAAGCUGCAGGGUGCAGCCUCCCACGUGCCCGAGGGCUUUGAUCCAACGGGACCUGCUGGGCUUGGGAGGCCAACUCCCGGCCUUUCCCAGGGACCAGGGAAGGAAACCUUGGAGAGCGCUCUCAUCGCCCUCGACUCGGAAAAACCCAAGAAGCUUCGCUUCCACCCAAAGCAGCUGUACUUCUCCGCCAGGCAAGGGGAGCUUCAGAAGGUGCUCCUCAUGCUGGUGGACGGAAUUGACCCCAACUUCAAAAUGGAGCACCAGAAUAAGCGCUCUCCACUGCACGCCGCGGCAGAGGCUGGACACGUGGACAUCUGCCACAUGCUGGUUCAGGCGGGCGCUAAUAUUGACACCUGCUCAGAAGACCAGAGGACCCCGUUGAUGGAAGCAGCCGAAAACAACCAUCUGGAAGCAGUGAAGUACCUCAUCAAGGCUGGGGCCCUGGUGGAUCCCAAGGACGCAGAGGGCUCUACGUGUUUGCACCUGGCUGCCAAGAAAGGCCACUACGAAGUGGUCCAGUACCUGCUUUCAAAUGGACAGAUGGACGUCAACUGUCAGGAUGACGGAGGCUGGACACCCAUGAUCUGGGCCACAGAGUACAAGCACGUGGACCUCGUGAAGCUGCUGCUGUCCAAGGGCUCUGACAUCAACAUCCGAGACAACGAGGAGAACAUUUGCCUGCACUGGGCGGCGUUCUCCGGCUGCGUGGACAUAGCCGAGAUCCUGCUGGCUGCCAAGUGCGACCUCCACGCCGUGAACAUCCACGGAGACUCGCCACUGCACAUUGCCGCCCGGGAGAACCGCUACGACUGUGUCGUCCUCUUUCUUUCUCGGGAUUCAGAUGUCACCUUAAAGAACAAGGAAGGAGAGACGCCCCUGCAGUGUGCGAGCCUCAACUCUCAGGUGUGGAGCGCUCUGCAGAUGAGCAAGGCUCUGCAGGACUCGGCCCCCGACAGGCCCAGCCCCGUGGAGAGGAUAGUGAGCAGGGACAUCGCUCGAGGCUACGAGCGCAUCCCCAUCCCCUGUGUCAACGCCGUGGACAGCGAGCCAUGCCCCAGCAACUACAAGUACGUCUCUCAGAACUGCGUGACGUCCCCCAUGAACAUCGACAGAAAUAUCACUCAUCUGCAGUACUGCGUGUGCAUCGACGACUGCUCCUCCAGCAACUGCAUGUGCGGCCAGCUCAGCAUGCGCUGCUGGUACGACAAGGAUGGCCGGCUCCUGCCAGAGUUCAACAUGGCGGAGCCUCCCUUGAUCUUCGAAUGCAACCACGCGUGCUCCUGCUGGAGGAACUGCCGAAAUCGCGUCGUACAGAAUGGUCUCAGGGCAAGGCUGCAGCUCUACCGGACGCGGGACAUGGGCUGGGGCGUGCGGUCCCUGCAGGACAUCCCACCAGGCACCUUUGUCUGCGAGUAUGUUGGGGAGCUGAUUUCAGACUCAGAAGCCGACGUUCGAGAGGAAGAUUCUUACCUCUUUGAUCUCGACAAUAAGGACGGGGAGGUUUACUGCAUCGACGCGCGGUUCUACGGGAACGUCAGCCGGUUCAUCAACCACCACUGCGAGCCCAACCUGGUGCCCGUGCGCGUGUUCAUGGCCCACCAGGACCUGCGGUUCCCCCGGAUCGCCUUCUUCAGCACCCGCCUGAUCGAGGCCGGCGAGCAGCUCGGGUUUGACUAUGGAGAGCGCUUCUGGGACAUCAAAGGCAAGCUCUUCAGCUGCCGCUGCGGCUCCCCCAAGUGCCGGCACUCGAGCGCGGCCCUGGCCCAGCGUCAGGCCAGCGCGGCCCAGGAGGCCCAGGAGGACGGCUUGCCCGACACCAGCUCCGCGGCUGCCGCCGACCCCCUAUGAGACGCCGCCGGCCAGCGGGGCGCUCGGGAGCCAGGGACCGCCGCGUCGCCGAUUAGAGGACGAGGAGGAGAGAUUCCGCACGCAACCGAAAGGGUCCUUCGGGGCUGCGCCGCCGGCUUCCUGGAGGGGUCGGAGGUGAGGCUGCAGCCCCUGCGGGCGGGUGUGGAUGCCUCCCAGCCACCUUCCCAGACCUGCGGCCUCACCGCGGGCCCAGUGCCCAGGCUGGAGCGCACACUUUGGUCCGCGCGCCAGAGACGCUGGGAGUCCGCACUGGCAUCACCUUCUGAGUUUCUGAUGCUGAUUUGUCGUUGCGAAGUUUCUCGUUUCUUCCUCUGACCUCCGAGGUCCCCGCUGCACCACGGGGUUGCUCUGUUCUCCUGUCCGGCCCAGACUCUUCUGUGUGGCGCCGCCGAAGCCACCGUUAGCGCGAGCUGCUCCGUUCGCCCUGCCCACGGCCUGCGUGGCUGGGGCCGAGUCCCAGGGGCCGCACGGAGGGCACAGUCUCCUGUCAGGCUCGGAGAGGUCAGGAGACCGACCCCACCACUAACUUUGGAGAAAAUGUGGGUUUGCUUUUUAAAGGAAUCCUAUAUCUAGUCCUAUAUAUCAAACCUCUAACUGACGUUUCUUUUCGAGGAAGUGGCUUGGUGGGUGCAGCCCCCGCCGGUUCCGUUGACGCUGGCACCUUCUGUUGAUUUUUUAAGCCACAUGCUAUGAUGAAUAAACUGAUUUAUUUUCUACCAUUACUGAACAUUAGGACAAACACAAAAUAAAAAACAAAACACAGACAACGGUGCUGAUUCUGGUGUGGUUUCUACUCACCACGUGAAAUAAACUAUCAACUGUAUAAAGAGAACAAAGUGAUUUUAGAAUAAAAUGCAGGAAAAACUUUUUUAAAGAUGUUAGUCUUGUAGCGUGAAUAAAUUUGCCAUCACCUUUUGUGUGGUGGCCUGGCAGGUCAUAUACUUUUUUUUGGCAUAUACCUUUUUAAAGACUGUAAUUAGUGCAGUAACAGUGGGGUUUUUUUUGUGCAACUCUUCUAAAAACAUUCAUAAUGCAGUCAUGUUUAUUUUUUUCUGUUAAAAUGUUUUUGACAGUUUUAAGAGCAGUCUUUUGGCUCUGACCAUUUCUUGUUCUGUUUCCAAUGAAAUCAAUAAAAAAAAAGAAGUACUUUAAA